ACUUUCACUCACCGCCUGUCCUUCCUGACACCUCACCAUGUGUACGGGAAAAUGUGCCCGCUGUGUGGGGCUCUCCCUCAUUACCCUCUGCCUCGUCUGCAUUGUGGCCAACGCCCUCCUGCUGGUACCUAAUGGGGAGACCUCCUGGACCAACACCAACCAUCUCAGCUUGCAAGUCUGGCUCAUGGGCGGCUUCAUUGGCGGGGGCCUAAUGGUACUGUGUCCGGGGAUUGCAGCCGUUCGGGCAGGGGGCAAGGGCUGCUGUGGUGCUGGGUGCUGUGGAAACCGCUGCAGGAUGCUGCGCUCGGUCUUCUCCUCGGCGUUCGGGGUGCUUGGUGCCAUCUACUGCCUCUCGGUGUCUGGAGCUGGGCUCCGAAAUGGACCCAGAUGCUUAAUGAACGGCGAGUGGGGCUACCACUUCGAAGACACCGCGGGAGCUUACUUGCUCAACCGCACUCUAUGGGAUCGGUGCGAGGCGCCCCCUCGCGUGGUCCCCUGGAAUGUGACGCUCUUCUCGCUGCUGGUGGCCGCCUCCUGCCUGGAGAUAGUACUGUGUGGGAUCCAGCUGGUGAACGCGACCAUUGGUGUCUUCUGCGGCGAUUGCAGGAAAAAACAGGACACACCUCACUGAGGCUCCACUGACCGCCGGGUUACACCUGCUCCUUCCUGGACGCUCACUCCCUUGCUCGCUAGAAUAAACUGCUUUGCGCUCUC